AGGAAUCCGAGGGGUCCGGGCGGGUCCCAACUGCCCGGCCCGGGGCGGAAGACCUCGGCGCCUUCUCGUGGGGUCAGGAGGGGAAGAGGCCCUUCCCCGUCACCUGAGAGCCGGCGCGGCCUCAGCCUUGAACUUUGAAUCCUGGGGGAAGAGGACAAAACCCGCUCCCGCGUGGCAGUUUGAGCCUCCGGAGCUUUCCCCCAUCUAACCUCUUCUGAUUCUUCGAACGUUCAGAGAACGGUAGCUAUUGUUCUCCCAUUUCACAGAUCAUGAAACGAGAUUCAAAGAAAGGCUGCGACUUGCCCAGGGUCACAUAGUUACUUAAAGGCUUAACUAGGAUUUAAACCCGGACUGCUUAUGAUCACACAAUGGAGGAAGGACUGAAUCCUCCCCCGAAGAAGGACCCCUCUAGGCGGCUCCCCUCUCUCCCGGGGGCUGGAGUAAGGCGGGUGGUCCAUAAGUCAUGAAGAAGGGGGUCGCACUCGUGUUGUUACUGAACUCCCGCUGCCCUCUCAGGACGCAGGUUAGCCCUUGGCUCUUGGGCAUCCAUCAAGUUUCUGGGCGCCCUGUAUGUCUUGAAUCUCCUGCUCACGCAGGGAACCCCUCAGGCCCGGGUGUGGGAAGCAGGGUGAAGGAGCCCCGACUCUUCGGAGGUCAUGCCCCCAGAGCGCAGGGGAAGGCCGAGUCGGCCACUGCCUGGCUGUUUGCUGGGACGAGGGGAUCGAGGGCCUGGCAGGGAUAGUACCUCUGAGACGCCUGCCUCCGGUGCUCCCUCCCGCCGUGCCUCCCUCCCUCGCUCGGUCCUCCGUAGCUCCUACUGGCGGAAAUCUCAGCAGGCCCUUUGUUUUCUGUUCCCCACAGCCUGGGCCGGCUCCUGCCCUCACAUAUGCUCCGGCACAAGCUGCAGGACUGCCCCCUCCCCCUCGGCAGUGUACACAUUUACUCUCCUACAGACACAGCCCCAUUGUCUCCGCCACUGCUCUUCCCCGGCCCUCUGGGUUCCAGAUGAGGCCAGCUGAGCCCCCCGACCCCCCCACAGCUGACCCACCCUGACUGCCUCGGGAAAGGAGCGGGGGAGGGGGCCGUCAGGCCGGAUUCCUUCCACCACCUUCUUGGCCCCCCUCUCUGCCACUCCCCCUCCCGGAAAUCCCCUCUUCCUCUCCCACUCCCACACCCCCUCCCCCCAUCCUGUCUUCUUCCCUGGGCCUUGGCCUCCACUGCACAGCCUGGAGCAGCCUCUGCCCUGCCUGUCCCCCAUCCCCCAGUGCCUGAGCUGUGCUGCUGAGGCUUCUGAAGGGGAGAGAGGUGGUUGGGUGGUCCCUGCUCCUCACCCGCCACGGUACAAGCACAAGUGAGGGUGUCCACAGCCCUGGCUGGGCCCCAAGCUGCAGGCUAAGCUUCUGCCUGAAGCCUAGGGACUUGCCUCUGUCCCCUCCCUUUCUCCAAAACCACUCAGUCAGCACAUUCCUGAAGCAGCCAAGUGGACCCCCUCCCCCUGGGCCCACCCCUCUUUCCCCACUCCUGCCUGAGCUGUUAGGUUGGCCCAGGAAGGCUGGUUGCCCUGUGGGCAGACACACCCCUUCAGUGCCUGUGGUUGUAUUGUCCUUGGCAUUGAAGCAUGGCCAGUGGUAGUGGGAUCAAGGGGAGGAGGUGGGUGCUAGAAAUCCUUGGGGCAGUUGGGGCAUGGACUGCCUGGGUCCUGGAGAGUGCCUCUAGAACUGGGCUCCCAUGUGGGCUCUGGUUCCGCCUGGAUCCCUGCCUGCCUUCCACCUACCUGACUCAGACCUGCCAGGAAUGCCCUGCCCCAGGGCCCUGAGUCCUGCUGGGUGAGCCAUUGCUCUGCCUGAGCCAUGCCAGGCAUGUGUGACUGGCCCUGGCUGGGGUCAGCAAGGGCAUGUCGACAGAAAGAAGCAUGCCAACAGGCUCCUUGGGUGCUGACGGCCAGUGAAGGAGUCUUCAAGUGCCCUGAGGACCAGCUUCCUCUGGACUAUGCCAAGUUCCCCCAUCCCUACCCCCAGAUCUACCCAGACCCGGAGCUGGAAGUACAAGUAUUGGGCCUGCCUAUCCGCUGCAUCCACAGUGAGGAGGGCUGCCGCUGGAGUGGGCCACUACGUCAUCUACAGGGCCACCUGAAUACCUGCAGCUUCAAUGUCAUUCCCUGCCCUAAUCGCUGCCCCAUGAAGCUGAGCCGCCGUGAUCUACCUGCACACUUGCAGCAUGACUGCCCCAAGCGGCGCCUCAAGUGCGAGUUUUGUGGCUGUGACUUCAGUGGGGAGGCCUAUGAGAGCCAUGAGGGUAUGUGCCCCCAGGAGAGUGUCUACUGUGAGAAUAAGUGUGGUGCCCGCAUGAUGCGGCGGCUGCUGGCCCAGCAUGCCACCUCUGAGUGCCCCAAGCGCACUCAGCCCUGCACCUACUGCACUAAGGAGUUCGUCUUUGACACCAUCCAGAGCCACCAGUACCAGUGCCCAAGGCUGCCUGUUGCCUGCCCCAACCAAUGUGGUGUGGGCACUGUGGCUCGGGAGGACCUGCCAGGCCAUCUGAAGGACAGCUGUAACACCGCCCUGGUGCUCUGCCCAUUCAAAGACUCCGGCUGCAAGCACAGGUGCCCUAAGCUGGCAAUGGCACGGCAUGUGGAGGAGAGUGUGAAGCCACAUCUGGCCAUGAUGUGUGCCCUGGUGAGCCGGCAACGGCAGGAGCUGCAGGAGCUUCGGCGAGAGCUGGAGGAGCUAUCAGUGGGCAGUGAUGGCGUGCUCAUCUGGAAGAUUGGCAGCUAUGGACGGCGGCUACAGGAGGCCAAGGCCAAGCCCAACCUUGAGUGCUUCAGCCCAGCCUUCUACACACAUAAGUAUGGUUACAAGCUGCAGGUGUCUGCAUUCCUCAAUGGCAAUGGCAGUGGUGAGGGCACACACCUCUCACUGUACAUUCGUGUGCUGCCUGGUGCCUUUGACAAUCUCCUUGAGUGGCCCUUUGCCCGCCGUGUCACCUUCUCCCUGCUGGAUCAGAGCGACCCUGGGCUGGCUAAACCACAGCACGUCACUGAGACCUUCCACCCCGACCCAAACUGGAAGAAUUUCCAGAAGCCAGGCACGUGGCGGGGCUCCCUGGAUGAGAGUUCUCUGGGCUUUGGUUAUCCCAAGUUCAUCUCCCACCAGGACAUUCGAAAGCGAAACUAUGUGCGGGAUGAUGCAGUCUUCAUCCGUGCUGCUGUUGAACUGCCCCGGAAGAUCCUCAGCUGAGUGCAGGUGGGGUUCGAGGGGAAAGGACGAUGGGGCAUGACCUCAGUCAGGCACUGGCUGAACUUGGAGAGGGGGCCGGACCCCCGUCAGCUGCUUCUGCUGCCUAGGUUCUGUUACCCCAUCCUCCCUCCCCCAGCCACCACCCUCAGGUGCCUCCAAUUGGUGCUUCAGCCCUGGCCCCUGUGGGGAACAGGUCUUGGGGUCAUGAAGGGCUGGAAACAAGUGACCCCAGGGCCUGUCUCCCUUCUUGGGUAGGGCAGACAUGCCUUGGUGCCGGUCACACUCUACACGGACUGAGGUGCCUGCUCAGGUGCUAUGUCCCAAGAGCCAUAAGGGGGUGGGAAUUGGGGAGGGAGAAAGGGUAGUUCAAAGAGUCUGUCUUGAGAUCUGAUUUUUUCCCCCUUUACCUAGCUGUGCCCCCUCUGGUUAUUUAUUUCCUUAGUGCCAGGAGGGCACAGCAGGGGAGCCCUGAUUUUUAAUAAAUCCGGAAUUGUAUUUAUUAAUUUGCUUCCAGCCUGACUUACCUGGGUUGGUUAGGUCCCUGGGAGGCUCAACCAAACUGAAGGCAAAGAAAGGACCAGUCAGAGAAGGGCCGCUGCCUGGGUCUGGCCCCAGGAUCCAGCUUACCUGCUGGCUCGCCCUCUGAUGGACGCCGGGAAAACUGCAUCGGGCUUUGUGUGGAAGACGGUCCCUGCCACUGCCCUCUGCCGAUGAAAUGCGGGAAGUGUAUGGCCUAGAUGUUUCAUAAGGCUGGAGUCCCUGGUCAGCCCCACCAGAUUAGUGCUUCUACCCUAGGCAGGGCUUUCUUGGUCUAAUGGUAAUAAGCACCGACACUGCUAAGCACUUUACGUGCAUUAUUAUUUCAUUGAAAAGAACUGUCAAGUGAAAUACUUUUUAGCACAGUAACUGGCUUUGUGGGCUCUAGAGAAGAGUUAAUGAGGCAGUGCAUGUUCUUGGCCCAGAGUAAGUGCUUAGUGAAUGCUUUCUAACUCCGAACCCCAGCCACAUCCAGGGACUGGGUGUUGAGCAAAAGGGGCCUUCAAGAUGUUCAAGGCACUUGGAUUUUCUCCUGUCUCUCAUCGGCUUUUCUUAACGGGCCUCAGUGGGUGCAUGUGAUUAUCCACGUUUCACCUAUGAAACAUGAACAGAGGAGACUGACUUAUCAGUGAUUCUUCCGCGGGUUCGGACAGGGCCUCGAUUCUGUUUUAAACUCCAGUAGUCCCUAGAAAUUGUAGCUCCCUCUAGUUGUGGCAAUAGGUGUGGGUCCUUGUGCUUGCUUUUGGCAAGUUUCUGAGCUACACAGGGCCUCCAUUACCGUCACUGGUGAAAUGCGGCUCACCUCCCAGAUUUGUUGUAAAGAUUAAAUGAACUGGUCAGCA